GAAGACAGUCCUUUUAUUUUAACCCAACAGCCUUGGGCCUUGGCUGUUUUUUCUGUAUCUCUUAACCCCUUGUGUGGGUAUUUUAGUGUUGAUCAUGCUCAAACAUAGUUUAUAUUAUAUCCAAAGUGUACAAAAUUUAGCCUCCAAGUGAUAUUCUAUGCAAUGAACUUUACUUUUUAAAAAUAGGUUCAAAGAGUAUGAAUGAGAUUUUUACCGUUAAAUUAUAGGAAACAUUUCAAUACUUGCCAUUUAUUUAUUUGCAUAUAAUACUAGAAUGCAUAUUGAUUUUGUAAAAAAUGAUUAUCCUAAUGUAUGCCAUUUGGGAUUACCUGUGGCUCUGCCAUCCUCCAUUAUCAGAGAUAAGUGAAAACUGGCUACACCUUUUUUUUUUUUUUUUUGAGACGGAGUCUUGCUCUGUCGCCCAGUCUGUAGCGUAGUCGUGCAAACUUGUUGCACUGCAGCCUCCGCUUCCAAGCAAUCCCCCUGCCUCAGCCUCCAACUAGCUGGGAUUACAGGCAUACGCCAUCACAGCCAGCUAAUUUUUGUGUUUUUAGUAGAGAUGGGGUUUCACCAUGUUGGCCAGGCUGAUCUCGAACUUCUGACCUCAGGUGAUCCACCCGCCUUGGCCUCCCAAAGUGCUAGGAUUCCAGGUGUGAGCUACUGCACCUGGCCUUGGCUACACUUUUUAGAUUUCUUUCCCAGCCGUUACUUCAGUUUUUUGGAAACUUAGAACUUGGUGGUCAUUUGUGCUUCUCUAAGUGUAUUCUUUUGAGAUGAAAUUUGUGUAAUAUAAAAUUAGCCAUUUAAAAGCAAACAAUUCAGUGACUGUUGGUACAUUCACAAUGUUGAGCAACUUCUACUUCUAGUUCCAAAAUGUUUUUAUCAUCCCUAAAGGAAACCCCAUACCCAUGAAGCAGUUUUGCUUCAGUCUCCGCACCCCCUCCUCUGACAACCACCAUUUCAUCUCAAUGGGUCUACCUAUACUGGACAUUUCAUAUAAAUGGAAUCAUACAAUGUGUGACCUUUUGUGUCUGGUUUCUUUCACUAAAUGUAAUGUUUUUGAGUUUCAUUUAUGUUGUAGAAUGUGUCAGAACUGUAUUCCCUUUUAUGAUUGGAUAAUAUUUCAUUGUGUGUAUAUACCCCAGUUUACCCAUUUAUCACUUGAUGGACAUUUGGGUUGUUUUAAUCUCUAGGCUGUUGUCAGUAGUGCUGCUGUGAACAUGUAUGUACAUGUAUUUGUUUGAAUACCAGUUUUCAGUUCUUCGGGUGUACACUAGGAGCAGAAUUACUGGGUCAUAUGGUAACCCUAUGUUUAACUUUUUGAGGAACUGCCAAACUGUUUUUCACAGUGACUGAAUCAUUUUACAUUCCCAGUGUAUGAGAGUUUCACUUUCUUUGCAUUUUCUCUAACAUCUAGGUGUUUUCUUGACAGUAAGAUGAGCAGGAUUAUCUUACAUAUAAUAUAUAAUUGAGGAAAUACGUAAAAUAUUUUGUGAACAAAGAGCCGAUAACCAGGUGCUACUGUCUGGGAUGAUAUGGUUCAAAUCCUUAUUUUUCAGUUAUGGGAAUAGUUGUCAGAGGCUGUGACUUACCUAAGCUGUAAGAAACAAAAUAAGCAAUAAAACCUAAGGUGUUCUUACCACCACUUAGAGCUUACCUCAAAGAUCCUCCAGGAUGGACAUCAUAACUUUGCGAGAAGCAGUUACUGGUACAGAAAAUAAAAAACAGCCAUUUGUGAGACAUACAGGACCACACUGUCUUUGAGAGCAAGGUACUGUUUCCUGUGACCUUUAGUACACUCAGUAGUAAGCAAUAAUUAGUCCUAAAUGGAGCACUGCUCUGGACCUGCCUAACAAUUCAUAAAGGGCUAACACUACCUGAUUUGAUGAUUUACUGUAAGGCUACAGUAACACAACAGCCUGGUAUUGGCAUAGGGGUGGACAAAUUGAUCGGUGGAAGAAAAUAGUAUAUCCAUACUUAAGUGGUCAUCUGAUUUUUGACAAAGGUGCAAAGGUAAUUCAAAGGAGAAAGGGUGGUCUUUUCAACCAGAGGUACUAUAAAACAAUUGGAUAGUCAUACACACAAAAAAAAGCCAAAAAAUUUUGAUUCAUACCUUGCACUAUGAACAAAAAUUAACUCAAACUGGCUGGGCAUGGUGACUCAUGCCUAUAAUCCCAGCACUUUGGGAGGCUGAGGCAGGAAGAGACCAGUCUGGGCAACAUAGUGAGACUUUGUCUCUAUUACAUAAAAAUAUAUAUAUAAAACCUAAACAAUAAAACUUCUAGAAGAAAACAAGAGAAAAUCUUUGUGACCUUGGGAUAGAUUUCUUAGGUGUUACGCUAGAAGAACAAACUGAUAUGUUGGACUUCAAAAUUUAAAACUGCUGUUCUUUAGUAAACACUGUUAAAAGAAUGAGAUGACAGAUCACAGGCUGGGAGGAAAUGUUUAUAAAGCAUAUAUUUGAUGAAAGAUUUGUAUUCAGAUUACAUAAAGAACUCUCAGGACUCAAUAAUAGCCUUUCCUUUUGGUGGUGCACAGCAGCAAUAUGGUGGUGAAAAUUUCUAAGAAGAGGAAGUUUGAUAGCAUCUUCAGAAAUAAACUGAGCGAAUUCUUCACUCAGAAGCUUGCAGAAGGUGACUACUCUGGAGCUGAGGUCCAAGUUAUGCCAACCAGGAUAGAAAUCACUACCUUAGCCUCCAGGAUGCAGAGUGUUCUUGGUGAAAAGAACCACCGGAUCUAUGAAUUGGCUGAGAUAGUUCAGAAGAGGUUUGGCUUCCUUGAGGGCAGGGAAAGCUUUAUGCUGAAAAGGUGGCCUAAAAUAAUUCUCUAUGCCAUUGCCCAGACAGAGUCUGUGCUGUAAACUACUAUUAGGGUUUGCUGUGAGGAGAGCCUUCUGUAGUGUGCUGUGGUUCAUUAUGGAGAGUGGGGCAAGAGCUACGAGGUCAUGGUGUCAGCGAAACUCUAAGGACAGAGAACUGAAUUCAUGAACUUUUGUGUGUGAUCUGAUGAUCCACAGCAGAGACCUUGUUAACUACUGCAUUGAUACUGCCAUCCACCAUGUGCUGCUAAGACAGGGUGUGCUGGGCAUCAAAGUGAAGCUCAUGCGUCCUGGGCCCAAGUGGUAAGAUUGGCCUUAAGAAUCCCCUGCCUGACCACGUGAGCACUGUAGACCCUAAAGAUGAGAUACUAUUCGCCAUGCCCAUCUCAGGACAGAUGGUUAGGAAGCCAUGCUCUACCCAGCCCCAACUGUGUAAUAGGGUCUCCUUGGCAGCUGGAUCUGGAGUCUGGAUGUUGCCUUGUAAAGACCUUUAAUAAAAUCUUUUAAGACAACAAAACACAACAACAAAAGCCCUUAAUAAUACAACAAACAACCCAAUUAAAAAUUGGGCAAAAGAUUUGAAUAGAUGUUUUAUCAGAGAUGAUAUACAGAUGACAAAUAAGCACAUGAAAAAAAUACUCAAUAUCAUUAAUUAUUAGGGAAAUUCAAUUAAAACCAUGAUGAGAUACCACUGCAAAUCUAUUAGAAUGGCUGAAAUAUAAAAGACUGGUCAUACCAAAUGUUGGUGAGGAUGUGGAGGAACUAUUGACGAGAAUGUUAAAUGGAGCCACCAUUUUGGAAAACAGCUUGGCUGUUCCUUAAAAAGGUAAAAGUGAUGGUUGACUCAGGAGACCGGAAGCGAGCCAUCAGUUCUGUGUGCACCUACAUUGUUUAUCAGUGUAGUCGGCCAGCUCCUUUACACUCCAGGGAUCUGCACUCCAUGAUAGUGGCAGCUUUUCAGUGUCUCUGUGUCUGGCUGACAGAGCACCCUGAUAUGCUUGAUGAAAAGGACUGCCUUAAGGAAGUACUGGAGAUUGUGGAACUGGGUAUCUCAGGAAGUAAGUCCAAGAACAAUGAGCAAGAGGUCAAGUACAAAGGAGAUAAGGAGCCAAACCCUGCAUCUAUGAGGGUAAAGGAUGCUGCUGAAGCCACCCUAACAUGCAUUAUGCAGUUGCUCGGCGCAUUUCCUUCACCUAGUGGUCCUGCCUCUCCUUGUAGUCUUGUGAAUGAGACCACUUUGAUUAAAUACUCCAGGCUGCCAACCAUAAACAAGCAUAGUUUCCGGUACUUUGUCUUGGAUAACAGUGUCAUCCUGGCAAUGCUGGAACAACCUCUUGGAAAUGAGCAGAAUGAUUUUUUCCCCUCUGUCACUGUGCUGGUCCGGGGAAUGUCUGGAAGACUUGCUUGGGCACAACAGCUUUGUCUUUUACCCAGAGGAGCAAAAGCAAAUCAGAAGCUUUUUGUACCUGAACCUCGCCCAGUUCCUAAAAAUGACGUUGGAUUUAAAUAUUCUGUGAAACAUCGGCCAUUUCCUGAAGAGGUGGACAAGAUUCCUUUUGUGAAAGCAGAUCUCAGCAUUCCAGAUUUGCAUGAAAUAGUCACUGAAGAAUUAGAAGAGAGACACGAAAAAUUAAGGAGUGGCAUGGCCCAGCAGAUUGCUUAUGAAAUACACCUUGAGCAACAGAGUGAGGAGGAAUUGCAGAAGAGAAGUUUUCCUGACCCAGUUACGGAUUGCAAGCCCCCGCCUCCUGCCCAGGAAUUCCAAACAGCCCGCCUUUUUCUCUCACACUUUGGAUUUUUGUCCUUAGAAGCACUGAAGGAACCUGCAAAUAGUCGUCUACCUCCUCACCUUAUUGCACUUGAUUCCACGAUACCUGGAUUUUUUGAUGACAUUGGGUAUCUGGAUCUCUUGCCAUGUCGUCCUUUUGACACAGUUUUUAUUUUCUAUAUGAAGCCAGGUCAGAAAACGAACCAAGAGAUUUUAAAGAAUGUGGAGUCUUCCAGAACUGUUCAGCCACAUUUCCUAGAAUUUUUGCUUUCCCUUGGCUGGUCAGUAGAUGUGGGCAGACACCCUGGUUGGACUGGGCAUGUUUCUACCAGUUGGUCUAUUAAUUGUUGUGAUGAUGGUGAAGGAUCUCAACAAGAAGAAGUGAUUUCCUCUGAAGAUAUUGGAGCUAGCAUUUUCAAUGGACAGAAGAAGGUGCUGUAUUAUGCUGAUGCCCUUACAGAAAUUGCUUUUGUGGUUCCUUCUCCUGUGGAGUCCUUAACUGAUUCAUUGGAAAGUAACAUCUCGGACCAAGAUAGUGAUUCAAAUAUGGAUCUUAUGCCAGGAAUUCUGAAACAGCCAUCCCUGACACUUGAGCUUUUCCCCAAUCAUACAGACAAUCUUAAUUCCUCACAGAGGCUCAGUCCCAGUUCCAGAAUGAGGAAGCUGCCUCAGGGUCGCCCUGUUCCUCCCCUUGGACCUGAGACAAGAGUUUCUGUAGUCUGGGUGGAACGCUAUGAUGAUAUAGAAAACUUUCCCCUCUCAGAGCUGAUGACAGAGAUCAGUACUGGUGUGGAAACUACUGCAAAUAGUAGCACUUCACUGAGAUCUACAACUCUUGAAAAAGAAGUUCCUGUCAUCUUCAUCCACCCUUUAAACACUGGAUUAUUCCGGAUAAAAAUUCAAGGAGCCACUGGAAAAUUUAAUAUGGUCAUCCCUCUUGUGGAUGGGAUGAUUGUCAGCAGGCGAGCUCUUGGCUUUCUGGUGAGGCAGACUGUAAUUAACAUUUGUAGAAGAAAGAGACUGGAAAGUGACUCCUACAGUCCCCCCCAUGUCCGCCGGAAACAGAAAAUCACCGACAUUGUCAACAAGUACCGGAACAAGCAGCUGGAGCCAGAGUUUUAUACUUCACUUUUCCAGGAGGUUGGACUCAAGAACUGCAGUUCUUAGACCACUGAAUUUCUAAGACUGUUGAACUCCAGUUUGGGAACUAUAACACAGCAGAACAGUUUGAUAGGUGAUCACUGUAAAAAUAAAAACAAAUCACUCCCAAGAGCUUACUGUUUAAUCACCAGAAUAGAAGAAACACAUUAUAACCCAUUUGAUAGAAGACUUUGGGCUAUCUAGUGAAAUGGGCUCCCAGACACAAUCACACUCCUGCUGAUAAUGAUGAUAUACAUUUUAGCCAUAAACUUUCUUUUAAAAGUGACAAUUUUAGUUAAACAUAAGCCUUUUGAGGAGAAAGGCUUUUAUGCAUCUCAGUUAAACACGUGCAUUGGUAGUAUCAACAAAUUUGCAAUAUAGAAGUUGAAGAUAGUUUUUUACCUCACUUUUUAGGAGGUUGUAUUCAAAAUUAAAAUCUCAGAAUCUUACAGGACAUUUAAAGACUCAUGUUGAUAGCAUGGAGGAGAAGGAAAGAAGUCACAGCCUUCUACUCAGUUGUAGGUCUUCUUGUCAUCCAGCUGUCACACUGACAAAAAGAAAAGAUGAUACAUGUUUUUUGCUCAGAUAAGAAGCCUGACAUUAAAAGAUGUCAUAUUUUUUUCUCCACAUUUCAAAAAGUUGUCCUUCUCAUCACUGCACAGAUCUGUCUGAAAGCCUCAGUUUCUGAGUGACCCAGGAACAGAUCAGAAAUGGAGCAUGGCCUUGUCCUUUAAUGGGGAUGCAAAUAAAGUUUGUGGGGUUAAAAGUUAUAAGACAGCAGUGAUACCCCACUCUCUCCAUUAUUGUCCAGCGGGGUGACAUAAUGACAGGUUAAAUAUUUGUGAUUCAUUGAUUAAAUAUUAUUUAAAGAAAUGUAAAUUCACAAUAAGGGUUGAAAAUUAUUUGGUUUCAUCCAUUGUCUCUUAUUUCAGGACCAAGCAGCAAACUGCAGUAGUUUGUGAAGGAUUCUAAUAUGGGGUUCAGGAAUAGCCUCUCAACGCUACUAAUUCAGAUCUCUCCCAGAGAACUACUGGAUUUCCUCAUAAUUGACAAACAUGAGUGACCACCUCUUUGGGUGGCUACUGUUAGAAAUGGCUGUUGUCAUGUUUUCUGGACUUUGCCAGCCAACAGAUCCCUGCCAGGUUUUGGAAAUACUUCUAUUACCUCGCUGCUACUUUUCUGCAGGGAUAAAACUUUUGAGGUGGCCAGACCCAGAACAUCCAAGGAUUCCUGUUACAGUGCUACAGUAUACACUGCUCAUUUAUCCUAUUCUCAUGUGCUUUCUUCUUUAGUAAGAUUAUUUUAAGAAAAUAAGUGAUAUUUAAAGUCCAAAGAGGAAUGAUCACAGUUGUAUAAGGGGUGUUUUCCCACUUGAACUCUGAUGUCAGUCGACUGUGGGUCAGAGCUACAACCAUCUGUUUGGUUUGAUGUUUUGGUGGUUUACUUACGGAGUGGGGAUAGUGUGAGACCUAAUUCCCUGUGCAAAUGUCUCUUAUUCCAGAAAUGUGCAUUUUGUCAUCUAUAAGCAAGAAAUAUGGGCAUAGCAGCUCUUGGUUUAAAGUUUGCCAUAACCUGUUCAUGUUUGUUUUAAGCUCAGGUAAAGAUAACCUCCUCUUUCUAUGACUCCAGUUUCCAUUCAGGUUAUAGUAUUAUUCAAUAGUUGAUUUUCUUUUUAAGCUGGGCAAUAAAUUGAUGUUUCCAGAUGGUAACAUGGGAGAGGGCAUAUAGGAUAAAGAUGAGCAAAUUCUACCCUAAAAAUGUUCUAGUAGUUCACAGGAAGAAGAUGAGGUUUAAUAACUUUCAAGGUAAUUCUAGAUUGACAUUUUGAGGGGAAAAUGGGCUCUUGUUCUAGUUGAAGUGAGCAGAGAAGGCUAUAAAUUAAUAUGUAACUUACAGCAUUCCAGAGGUUAAAAAUAACUGAUGCAGAUGUACUUCUUCAGUGUGAUUCUUCAGAUCAAACUUUUACUUUUGGCAUAGUUAAUUUCAGAAAAAUGUGCUGUAUGUGUGUGUGUAUGAGGGUUGGUCUUGCUGAUCCUUCAGUUAGCUCUAAAUUCUGGCAACUCCUUGUAAUUCCAAUGUAUUUGAUACAUGAACAAUCAUGUUGAAUGCAUUUGUGAUCUGGGAGACUUCCUCGUCUUCCAGGGAAGGAAGGAUGUGCAGCCCCUGAAGGCAUGAAACUCCCAGUGUGUACGGAGCCAGUGGAAUAUGGGAUACCCAUACCUUACCAGGCGCUGGUUCCUUCUGCUCACAAUAACAUCUGCCCAAAGAGGGAGUGGGAAGAACGCUUAGCUCUUUCACUAGUAUGGAUUUGAGUUCAUGGUCACUAUUUUUACCCACCUGCCUUUGUUAAAAAUCACUUUGAGUAGAAUAGCACUGGAGGAACAUAUUUAGCACCUAAUAUUAAUAUUUAGUAGUCCAUUGAUAAAUUUGCCAGCAUAUGUUCUAGCCUCUGGGGGGAAACCAGGACCACUUUUGUCUGUGGCUUAAACAGUUCAGUUGCUAUAUCUGUUGGGUAUGCCGGGGGUGGAUGAGUGUGGCAUUCCGUGAAGAGGAAGGUGGUAAGUAAGGUUUCCCUUCUACUGCCUUCUUAAGUUGCAGGAGGGAGCUUUUCUCCUCCCCUCUGGUUGGGAGCACUGAGGACAGUGAGGAGGGCUUUUACCUUGUUAAUCCUUUCCUUAUUUAGCUAGCUUUCCUUUUUGUCUAGGGCUUCCUCUUGAGACCCUCUUCCAUCCAUUGGGCCUUUGAAAGGACUAAUCAGACACACACACACACACACACACACACACACACACUCGCAUACUCAUGCACAUUUUCCUUCAUUUCCAGAUCCUUUAUUUCAGAGCAGCCCAUUUUCCUCUGGAUUCAUUGAUGAAUACAAGUACCCACACCUUUGGCCAGUAAUGUCAGUUACCUGCUGCAGGUUCUGUGUAUGAGGCCUUCAUGAACGGUUACCUUCUCCAUACACUAGGGAAGCAUUUGUCAGACUCUGCAGACUGGGUUCUAGAGAGGCAGAGUCUUUAAGAGUAUUCAUUUCUUCUGGAAGGUGGAGCUUUACCCAAAGUGGAAGUUAGCCUUGCUCAAAGAUGUGUUUUGUGGUAGGUGGUAAAAAUAAAUAAAUAAAUAAAUAAUAAAAAAAGAAACAUGUAUUGGAGGUAAUUUGACACUGCUGCUGGCAGUAGUUCUCUAUUCACCAUUUUAAAGCCCAUUCAGGUUCUCUCUUCCUGAAAAGAACUGAUUGCUGUGUUUACAUGAAAUGACAUUGGAGUCAGAUGGUCUGUUUUAAAGAUUUCCAUGACAGCCUCUUUUCCUGAGUUGGAGAGAUUGGAGGUGGUCUAUCCGUACGAUGUGGAAUCAAACGGUGGGUUUCUUAGUAGCUAAAGAAGCCAUGUACUUCUAGUGUGUUUCUCAGAAUAUCAACUCAUGUUCUUCAGAUGCUUUUCUUUUUUUAAUGGUGAGGGAAAAGGUAUAAUUUGGGAUUCCACAGUGCCUUGCAUAUAGUAGGCGCCCAGUAAAUACUUGUUGAAGCAAACCAAGUUUCCCAAGUCCUCAUCUCUUAUAGUGACCAAGACAUCUUUCUCCUCUGAAGGGCUUGGCAGUUGUGGCUAAAAAAUAAGCAGUAUCAUUAUUUGCUUGAAAUCAUAUAUACAGUUUGUAUGAAUUUCAGUAUGUUGCCAAGACAUGAUUUUUUCUUAUUGUAUUUUCUGUAAAUAUUUCUGGCACUGAACUGUAAAGUAAAGGCAAAGUGUAAAUAUGAAGGCGUGCCCGUGCCCCUUGCCUCCUGUGUUUCAUCUUCGUCGGUUAGGGAAGAAGGUCCAGAGGUUUGUUUGUAUUUAUGCCGAUCCUUUGUCCAGAAGAAGCCCAUGGAAUAUUGAAUGUAAUACAUUUAGUCAAUUAAAUUUUAAGGAGAUUCUUAUCUAA